ACAGAACGAGCGAGCGAGCGAGCGGAGAGGCGGCUACAGCCUGAGCGCCGGGCCGGUAGCGGCCGCGCCGGCGAGCGGACUAGCGGGCGGCGAGCAGCGCGGAGCGCGCGGGGCACCGAGGAGCGGGCGCGGCGGGCACCGCGCGAGGCAGCCGGAGCUCUCGGAAAGGCCAGAGCGGCGCCGCCCCCGCUGCCCCUGCGGGGCCCCGGCUGGGAGCCCGACGAGGGAGCGGGCGGCAUGGCCCGGCGGCCCGGGGCGCGGGGGCGCUAGGCCCCCGGAGGGGCGUCCCCAGCCUCGCCGCUGCCGCCGCCGCCCUCCGCAGCCGCGCGCCCCGCCCGCUCCAGCCGCCCCCGGGGCCGCCACCGGCCCAUGAGCCCCGGCCUCAAAGUUUGCGGCGGGCGGGCGGGCGCGGAGCCUCCAAGAUGCCGUUCCACCCGGUGACGGCGGCGUUGAUGUACCGGGGCAUCUACACCGUGCCCAACCUGCUGUCGGAGCAGCGCCCGGUGGACAUCCCGGAGGACGAGCUGGAGGAGAUCCGAGAGGCCUUCAAGGUGUUUGACCGUGACGGCAAUGGCUUCAUCUCCAAGCAGGAGCUGGGCACAGCCAUGCGCUCACUGGGUUACAUGCCCAACGAGGUGGAGCUGGAGGUCAUCAUCCAGCGGCUGGACAUGGAUGGUGAUGGUCAAGUGGACUUUGAGGAGUUUGUGACCCUUCUGGGACCCAAACUCUCCACCUCAGGGAUCCCAGAGAAGUUCCAUGGCACCGACUUUGAUACUGUCUUCUGGAAGUGCGACAUGCAGAAGCUGACGGUGGAUGAGCUGAAGCGGCUGCUCUACGACACCUUCUGCGAGCACCUGUCCAUGAAGGACAUAGAGAACAUCAUCAUGACGGAGGAGGAGAGCCACCUGGGCACAGCCGAGGAGUGUCCCGUGGAUGUGGAGACCUGCUCCAACCAGCAGAUCCGCCAGACUUGCGUGCGCAAGAGUCUCAUCUGCGCCUUCGCCAUCGCCUUCAUCAUCAGUGUCAUGCUCAUUGCGGCCAACCAGGUGCUGCGCAGUGGCAUGAAGUAGACGCCACCUGGAUGCCCCAUCCACCGCAUGCGGUGCCCGUGGCCCGCCCCACACCACCGCCGCCUGCAGACCUCUCCCUUGGCCGGCUCCCUGGGCCGCCAUCUGCGUGUACUUCAGGGCCUGGGUAUCCAGCGAGCCCUCCCCACCCACCCACGGUCCUCACCUGGAGCUGUGGCCUGGCUGUGGAGGGCCGGGUGGUGGCUCUGAGGAUGGUCCCCAGCCCCACCCUGUCCCCACCCUGGCCUGUAAGGAGCACUCACUCUUCCUACCAUCCAGGGGCUCCUGGGAAAUUAAGGAGGGAUUUGCACAGGAACCCCCAGGACCCAGUCGCUGCUGUGGUCCCUUGGGCAGGAGCGGGCACCCUGUGCCUUGAGACAGCAGCCUAUCUGGGGCCACACAGCCAACCCAGCCCUGGUCCCUGAGGUCUGCCCAGGGCACAGGGCACAGGCAGGGACAGAAAGCCUUCUCCUGGGGGAGGGUGGGAAGCCAGGGUGUCCUGGGCCUUGCUGCCUGGCAUAGCCUGAGGAGGCCCCUGGUCUUCUCCUUGGGCCCCUUCCUCUGACCCUCGUUGGACCCCAACCCAGACCCCCUUUUCUCCAUGUACCUGCUGGGCCAGCCCAUUUCACAGGUGAGGAACCCGAGGCUCAGGGCCCCGAGACUUGGCCUCAGUUCUUCCUUCCACAGGGAUUUUCAGGAAAGGCAGAAGCUCGUGGAGGAUGGGCAUCUGAGGUGGCCCUGCAGCCCCCCACCUUCUGGCCCUCCCACCAGAGGCCCAGCUACCAAGGCCACAUUGUCCACCACCCCAGCCUAGAGCCUAGAACUGUAGUCCAGCUGAGGAAGGAGGCAGAGCUGGGGCCUGAAGGCUCUGAGCAGCCUCCAGCCAGGGGGCUCCUCCAGGGCUGAACUUUGGGAGGGCCCCUGUACUACCUCCUGGGCCAAGAAACUGGCACAGCCCCACACUGUCAGUGCCAAGAGGCUGCGCCAGGCCACUCUCUCAGCCCAGGGCCUGCCCUCCUGUCCUCCCACUUCUCUACGCCCUCAAGGUUGGAGACCCCGCUCCCAUGCCCCAGCUGUGCCAUCCCAAAUACUUGGGCAGCAGCUCAGCAUGGGCAGACAUGGGGGCUGUGGAUUCUUCCAGGGCGGGGAUGGCAGAUGGAGCCCUUGGGCUCCUUGGGCCUAGAGCCACUUCUUACCAGGCAACGGGCACAGCCACCCUGGCACACCCUCUGCCUGGCCGUGCUGAACCUCUGCUGGUCCCAAGGGAGAAGGGAGUGAGCGUGGGUCACCUGGGGAAAAUCUCAUCUGAUUCCCUCCUUGCCCGACCUCUGCUAGGGGCUGGAGAACAGAGCUCAGAGCACCCAGUGUAGGGAAACACAGCCAGACCACUGUGGUGACAGACUUUCUUUAUAAACAUUUGGAAGUUUUCUCCCCCAUCUUCUUAAGAAGCAGGGGGGCAGGUGGAGGAGAGUGAGGGGAGAGCUGCCCGGUGCAGACCCAGGACGAGGGCUGCACUUGGUGUGGCCGUGUCCUGAGCCUCAGUGAGGCUGGGCAGAUGGUCUCGGAGCCUCCAUGGGGCGUAGCAGGAACCGGGCUUGGCUUCCUAUUGUGACUGAUGAGAAAAGUGACCACGUGGGGGUCAGUCGGGGGCAAGGGGCUCAGCCCCACUGGACUCUGGGCUGCAGAGGCCACCCCCCAGGUGGGGGUGCCCGCAGGGAUGGAGGCAGCUCCUGAACUGGUGGCCAGCCCACGGGGUACUGGAAGACAGUGGUUCUGAUGGGUUCAGCCCUAGAGAGAGAGAGAGAAGCGGGGAGAAUAAGAGUGCACUACAGCCCAGGCUUAUGCCACCCCCAGCCCACCUGCCUCACCACCCUGGCUGUGGGGAGGGUCAGCUGCCUGCAUGACUUUUCUGGAAGGCAGAGCCUCGAAAAUAGGCAGACCGUUUGAGCCAGCGACCUCACCUCUAGGAACUGAGCCCAAGGAAAUAGCGGGGUUGCAGGCAGACAUUGAGCUGCGAGACAAUGGGAAUAACCUUCGUGUCCACCUGUGGGGGACUGAUUCAAUACAUAUGCACGUCCACAGCAGAGAAUGCCAUGCGGCCUGUGUAAGAAUUAAGGCAGAUUUAUAUGCACUGAUGAGGAAAGACAUACUGUGUGAUAGGGAGAAAAAGCAGCUUAUAAAAUAAUGUAUAUAGCAUGAUACUAUUUUUGUUUAAAAAUAUAUAAAAUAUAUAAAUGCAUAAAAAAAUCCUGGAAGACACAGCAAAA